GCCGCCGCCGCUGCUGCUGCACUGACGGCGGGUGCCCGCGCCUCAGGUGAGUGAGCGCCUCCGCCCGGCCCGCGGGGGGCGCGCGGCGCCGCAUUCGGGGGCGUCGCUCCUUUGCCCUGCUCCUUCCCCGCAUCAUCUCCGCGGCACGGCGAGGCCCUGGUGGCCCGUGCUGCUUGCCUCCCCCGUGCCCCCGGGGCCCUCUGCCCCGCCCCGCCCGCCCGCCGGACCCAGGUCAGCCCGGCUUUCCUCGGCCGCUCCCCGCGCCCAGCCCGCCGGCGACAGCGUGUGGGUAGCAAGAGAGCCUCCCUCCGGGCUCAACACCCUGGGUCACAGGGACGCCCCCCGCAGGCGCGAACCCUUCUCUCGCUCUGGCUCUGCAGGCGGCAGAGCUUGGUGGGCCUUGGGGUUGCUCAUCCAUCUACCUCGCCCGCUCCAAGAGCCCAGAUGCUUGGAAGAGGGGCCGUGAGCAGCCCUUGCACCCGUCCGGCCCCAGAGCAGCAGAGGGCAUCCUCUAACGGGACCCUACGACUACCCUACCGGGGAGAGGCUUCUUAGCCCCACUUAACAGCCGAGGAAACUGAGGCACGGAAAGAGUUACUGAUUUAUUCUUGAGAUUCCUCUACUCUCGUUAUCUGACCUCAUGGAUGAACUUCAGGAUGUUCAGCUCACAGAGAUCAAACCACUUCUAAAUGAUAAGAAUGGUACAAGAAACUUCCAGGACUUUGACUGUCAGGAACAUGAUAUAGAAACAACUCAUGGUGUGGUCCACGUCACUAUAAGAGGCUUACCCAAAGGAAACAGACCAGUUAUACUAACAUAUCAUGACAUUGGCCUCAACCAUAAAUCCUGUUUCAAUGCAUUCUUUAACUUUGAGGAUAUGCAAGAGAUCACCCAGCACUUUGCUGUCUGUCAUGUGGAUGCCCCAGGCCAGCAGGAAGGUGCACCCUCUUUCCCAACAGGGUAUCAGUACCCCACAAUGGAUGAGCUGGCUGAAAUGCUGCCUCCUGUUCUUACCCACCUAAGCCUGAAAAGCAUCAUUGGAAUUGGAGUUGGAGCUGGAGCUUACAUCCUCAGCAGAUUUGCACUCAACCAUCCAGAGCUUGUGGAAGGCCUUGUGCUCAUUAAUGUUGACCCUUGCGCUAAAGGCUGGAUUGACUGGGCAGCUUCCAAACUCUCUGGCCUGACAACCAAUGUUGUGGACAUUAUUUUGGCUCAUCACUUUGGGCAGGAAGAGUUACAGGCCAACCUGGACCUGAUCCAAACCUACAGAAUGCAUAUUGCCCAAGACAUCAACCAAGACAACCUGCAGCUCUUCUUGAAUUCCUACAAUGGACGCAGAGACCUGGAGAUCGAAAGACCCAUACUGGGCCAAAAUGAUAACAAAUCAAAAACAUUAAAGUGUUCUACUUUACUGGUGGUAGGGGACAAUUCGCCUGCAGUUGAGGCUGUGGUCGAAUGCAAUUCCCGCCUGAACCCUAUAAAUACAACUUUGCUAAAGAUGGCGGACUGUGGGGGACUGCCCCAGGUAGUUCAGCCUGGGAAGCUCACCGAGGCCUUCAAGUACUUUUUGCAGGGAAUGGGCUACAUACCAUCUGCCAGCAUGACUCGGCUCGCCCGAUCACGAACCCACUCAACCUCGAGUAGCCUCGGCUCUGGAGAAAGUCCCUUCAGCCGGUCUGUCACCAGCAAUCAGUCAGAUGGAACUCAAGAAUCCUGUGAGUCCCCUGAUGUCCUGGACAGACACCAGACCAUGGAGGUGUCCUGCUAAGCAGAUGCUCCUCCCCUGGACCAUUGCAAGUCCAUCCUUCAAAUGACCACUCCAUAAUAUAACAUUUCAUCCAGUAAACUGGCCUCUACUAUCUUUAACUCAUGCAUGGCCACUGAACCUCUCUCUAGUAGCCUGGAUUUAUCAUUCUCUCUGCCUGCCCACCCCCUUUUUUGUAUAGCCCAAGAACCACUUCCAUGCCAUACUGUAACAUUCCAACAUCUUUAGCUGAUCAGAUCUCUCCAUAUCCUCUCUUGCCAGCUUUUUCCCGUGCUCCCCCAACUAUGUAUCAGAUAAGAUUCUUUGAUCCCGACUCUGUGUGUGCGAGCACGCGUGUCUGUGUUUGUGUGUGCAUAGUUCUGUGGUUUUAGACACGCUUUCUUGUAGUGCUUCUGCAAAAAACAAAAAAGGGACUUAUUUUGCAUUCUCAAUGGUGUUUUUAAGGGAAUUAGGCAGAACAGAUUUCUAGGUUGGGUAGGCCACUGCAUUCUCUUUUGUUUGCAAAUUGGUCAACAAAAUUUGCAAAGUGAUUUCAGGAGAGAGCAGCUUUGAGGAAUGUGGAAAAUCAUAAUUGCCGUCUGGACCAUUGAUUGAUUGUGACCAGUAGCAGAAGGGUGCCUGUUACAUAGAGAGGCUCCUUCUGUCCAAAUGAAUUUCUGUAUACUCUUCUAUAAAUAAAAGGGAGGAAUAUAUUCUGCUGGAAGCCCAUGAACCAUCGCUGAGGUUCUGAUACAACAUAGAGUUUUUUCCAAGGAGUGAAUGUGGUUUAAUUACUGGACUCUCUUAGCACAGGAAGGUGGAAACAAAAUGCCAGGCCUCUGCUCUGAAGAGCAAAACUGCUGUCGCUGCAGUAUCUGAUACCAGACAUCCACAUAUCCACAAGAAGUGCCUCUUAGGUCUGUGACAGAGAGUGUGUCUCCAUUCCUCAGUUCCCAGAAAGGGGAGAGGUUUGGCCUAAAAAGCAUGUAGAUGGGGGAGAAAUGGGUGGGGGGAGAGGAACAGCCAUUAACACAGUAUCAUGUUUAACAAGUAUAGCCUUGAUUUCAGUAGAUGUAAUGGAAGCCAAAUUAAAUUGAUACAGAACCCAUUUCUCAGAGUCUUUUUUUUUUUUUGAGACAGAGUCUCGCUGUUACCCAGGCUGGAGUGCAAUGGCGCAAACUUGGCUCACUGCAACCUCUGCCCCCUGGGUUCAAGCGAUUCUCCUGCCUCAGCCUCCCGAGUAGCUGAGACUACAGGCACCUGCCACCAUACCCAGCUAAGUUAUGUAUUUUUAGUAGAGAUGGAGUUUCACCAUGUUGGCCAGGCUGGUCUCAAACUCCUGACCUCAGGUGAUCCACCUGCCUCAGCCUCCCAAAGUGCUGGGAUUACAGGCAUGAGUCAUUGCUCCCAGCCAUUAGAAAGAUUGUUAAUCCUAUGAACUCCCUUUUGUAGGAGAGAAAGGGCCAAUCUGUAGGGGUAGCCCUGUCCAGGUAAAGUUGUUUUCAGCCUCAUGUCUACUGUUAGGUGAGGGAGUCACAGCCAGACAGAGAGUAUUGCUGGAGGGUGAGAGAAUUGUGGAGACCAACUACCACAUAGCAAGAGCCCAGCUCUUGGGAGCAUUGAGAUGUAAGCUCAGGGUUACACAGUUCCAAAUCUUGGGAAGGGGCUUUUCAGACAGACUGUUUGCUUUCUGCUGAGAUAAGGAAUGCAUCACUCUGCCAGAGUAUGACUUUUUACAGAUUAUUAAAUAAAGCUGCAUAUGUCUCAUUGUUA